AGUGCCGCCACUGGAACCAGGAGAUGCGGCGCAGGAGCUGUCGCUGUGUUUGCUUUAACCUGAGUCUUGUUCCUUAUUGUGGUUCCUGCUGUGGUUUUGAUCAUGUUGUUACCCUCGGACGUAGCCCGGCUUGUAUUGGGUUACUUACAGCAAGAAAACCUCAUUUCUACCUGCCAGACUUUUAUUUUGGAAAGUUCAGAUUUAAAAGAAUAUGCAGAACAUUGUACAGAUGAAGGGUUUAUUCCAGCCUGCUUACUGUCCUUAUUUGGAAAAAACUUGACAACAAUUUUAAAUGAGUAUGUAGCUAUGAAAACAAAAGAAACAUCAAAUAAUGUCCCAGCAAUAAUGUCAUCUCUAUGGAAGAAAUUGGACCAUACACUUUCUCAGAUCAGGAGCAUGCAAAGUUCCCCAAGGUUUGCUGGCAGUCAGAGAGCCCGAACGAGAACUGGAAUUGCAGAAAUCAAACGGCAGAGAAAGCUUGCAUCUCAAACAGCUCCAGCCAGUGCAGAGUUGCUCACUUUACCUUACCUUUCAGGACAGUUUACCACUCCUCCUUCCACAGGUACACAGGUUACUCGACCAAGUGGCCAAAUUUCAGAUCCAUCGAGGUCAUAUUUUGUAGUGGUCAACCACUCACAGUCACAAGAUACUGUAACCACUGGAGAAGCUUUAAAUGUCAUUCCUGGUGCUCAGGAAAAGAAAGCACAUGCCAGUUUAAUGUCUCCCGGUAGACGCAAAAGUGAAUCUCAGAGAAAAAGUACCACUUUGUCUGGCCCUCAUUCAACAAUACGGAAUUUCCAAGAUCCAAACGCUUUUGCAGUAGAAAAACAAAUGGUUAUUGAAAAUGCACGAGAAAAAAUACUAAGCAACAAAUCUCUUCAAGAAAAGCUAGCAGAAAACAUAAAUAAAUUUUUAACUAGUGAUAACAAUAUUGCCCAAGUACCUAAGCAAACAGAUAACAACCCUACGGAGCCAGAGACUUCAAUUGAUGAAUUCCUAGGACUUCCGAGUGAAAUUCACAUGUCUGAAGAAGCUAUACAGGACAUAUUGGAACAGACAGAAUCAGACCCAGCAUUUCAGGCACUCUUUGAUCUCUUUGACUAUGGCAAAACAAAGAAUAAUAAAAAUAUAUCACAAAGUAUUUCCAGUCAACCUAUGGAAUCCAAUCCCAGUAUAGUCUUAGCAGAUGAAACUAAUCUAGCAGUUAAAGGUUCUUUUGAAACAGAAGAAUCUGAUGGUCAGUCUGGUCAGCCCGCUUUUUGUACAUCCUAUCAGAAUGAUGACCCAUUAAAUGCUUUGAAGAAUAGCAACAACCAUGAUGUGCUUAGACAAGAAGACCAGGAAAAUUUUUCCCAAAUAAGUACCAGCAUACAGAAAAAGGCCUUUAAAACAGCUGUACCCACUGAACAGAAGUGUGACAUUGACAUUACCUUUGAGUCCGUGCCUAAUUUGAAUGACUUUAACCAAAGAGGGAAUUCUAAUGCUGAAUGUAAUCCACAUUGUGCUGAAUUAUACACCAAUCAGAUGUCCACUGAAACUGAAAUGGCUAUAGGGAUUGAAAAGAACUCUUUGUCUUCAAAUGUACCGAGUGAAUCUCAGUUACAGCCUGAUCAGCCUGAUAUACCAAUAACUUCAUUUGUUUCACUUGGUUGUGAAGCUAACAAUGAAAACUUAAUUCUCUCUGGGAAGAGUUCUCAACUUUUAUCCCAAGAUACUUCAUUAACUGGAAAGCCAUCUAAAAAAAGUCAAUUUUGUGAAAAUUCUAAUGAUACAGUAAAACUUAAAAUUAAUUUUCAUGGUUCCAAGUCAUCAGAUUCUAGUGAAGUUCACAAGAGUAAAAUAGAAAUUAAUGUGUUAGAACCAGUUAUGUCACAGCUAUCAAAUUGCCAAGAUAAUUCUUGUCUUCAAAGUGAAAUACUACCUGUGUCUGUUGAAAGUUCACAUUUAAAUGUAUCUGGACAAGUAGAAAUUCAUCUUGGAGAUUCGCUGUCUUCUACUAAACAACCAUCUAAUGAUUCAGCAUCUGUUGAGUUAAAUCAUACAGAAAAUGAAGCUCAGGCAUCCAAGUCUGAGAAUUCACAGGAGCCUUCAUCUUCUGUAAAAGAAGAGAAUACUAUUUUUCUCUCUUUAGGUGGAAAUGCUAACUGUGAGAAAGUUGCACUGACGCCUCCAGAAGGCACUCCUGUAGAAAACAGUCACUCUCUUCCUCCAGAAUCUGUGUGUUCUUCAGUGGGAGAUUCUCACCCUGAGUCCCAAAAUACUGAUGAUAAACCUUCUAGCAACAACUCAGCAGAGAUAGAUGCAUCAAAUAUCGUCUCUCUCAAAGUUAUCAUUAGUGAUGAUCCAUUUGUUUCCUCAGAUACUGAACUUACCAGUGCUGUUUCUAGUAUUAAUGGAGAAAACCUGCCAACUAUAAUCUUGUCUUCUCCUACUAAAUCACCUACUAAAAAUGCAGAACUAGUUAAAUGCCUAUCUUCAGAAGAAACUGUAGGUGCUGUUGUAUAUGCCGAAGUAGGGGAUUCAGCCUCAAUGGAACAGAGUCUUUUAACAUUCAAAUCUGAAGACUCUGCAGUAAACAAUACUCAGAAUGAAGAUGGCAUUGCUUUUUCAGCUAAUGUUACACCAUGUGUUUCCAAGGAUGGAGGAUAUAUACAGUUGAUGCCAGCCACAAGCACAGCUUUUGGCAAUUCAAAUAACAUUCUGAUAGCUACCUGUGUGACUGAUCCAACAGCGUUAGGAACAUCUGUAAGUCAGUCUAAUGUAGUGGUGUUGCCUGGAAAUUCUGCACCUAUGACUGCUCAACCUCUACCACCUCAGUUACAGACACCACCAAGGUCAAACAGUGUAUUUGCUGUCAACCAAGCUGUGUCACCAAACUUUUCACAAGGAUCUGCCAUAAUAAUUGCCUCUCCAGUCCAGCCUGUACUCCAAGGAAUGGUAGGGAUGAUCCCAGUAUCUGUGGUUGGACAGAAUGGAAAUAACUUUUCUACUCCUCCUCGGCAGGUUCUUCAUAUGCCUUUGACAGCACCUGUAUGCAAUAGAAGUAUCCCUCAAUUCCCCGUCCCUCCAAAAUCUCAGAAGGCUCAGGGACUAAGAAACAAGCCUUGUAUAGGAAAACAAGUAAAUAAUUUGGUGGAUUCGUCAGGUCAUUCAGUUGGAUGUCAUGCACAAAAAAAUAGUUUUGUUUUGUUUUGUUUUAGAACUGAAGUUUCUGACAAAAGUAUUGCCACAGAUCUUGGGAAAAAAUCAGAAGAAACCACAGUUCCCUUCCCAGAAGAGAGUAUAGUUCCAGCUGCUAAACCAUGCCACAGACGUGUACUCUGUUUCGACAGCACUACUGCUCCUGUGGCAAAUACGCAGGGGCCAAACCAUAAGAUGGUGUCCCAAAACAAAGAAAGGAAUGCAGUCUCUUUUCCUAAUCUUGACUCACCCAAUGUGUCCUCCACCUUAAAACCCCCUUCUAAUAAUGCUAUCAAAAGAGAGAAAGAGAAGCCUCCUCUGCCUAAGAUUUUAUCUAAAUCGGAAAGUGCCAUUAGCCGGCAUACCACCAUAAGAGAAACUCAAUCAGAAAAGAAAGUUUCACCAACAGAAAUUGUGCUUGAAUCUUUCCAUAAAGCAACAGCUAAUAAGGAGAAUGAAUUAUGCAGCGAUGUAGAAAGACAGAAAAAUCCAGAAAAUUCAAAACUAUCUAUUGGGCAGCAAAAUGGGGGUUUGCGAAGUGAGAAAUCUAUAGCUUCACUGCAAGAAAUGACCAAAAAACAAGGCACAUCUUCAAACAAUAAAAAUGUACUUUCAGUAGGUACAGCUGUGAAGGAUCUAAAACAAGAACAAACUAAAUCCGCCAGUUCUUUGAUUACCACAGAAAUGUUACAGGAUAUACAGAGGCACAGCUCAGUAAGUAGGCUUGCUGAUAGUAGUGAUUUACCUGUGCCCCGGACACCUGGCUCAGGGGCAGGGGAAAAACAUAAAGAAGAACCUAUAGAUAUUAUCAAGGCCCCCUCUAGUAGGCGUUUCAGUGAAGACAGUAGUACAUCAAAAGUAAUGGUCCCUCCUGUCACCCCAGACUUGCCUGCCUGCAGCCCUGCCAGUGAAACAGGAAGUGAAAACAGUGUAAAUAUGGCUGCCCACACAUUAAUGAUUCUCUCCAGGGCAGCCAUUUCUAGGACUACUUCAGCAACUCCUCUGAAAGAUAACACACAACAGUUUAGAGCAUCUUCAAGGAGCACCACAAAAAAGCGGAAAAUUGAGGAAUUAGAUGAACGUGAGCGAAACUCUCGUCCUUCUAGUAAAAAUCUUACAAAUUCAUCAAUACCAAUGAAAAAGAAGAAAAUUAAGAAAAAGAAGCUUCCCAGUUCAUUUCCAGCAGGAAUGGAUGUAGACAAAUUUUUGUUAUCAUUGCAUUAUGAUGAGUAAACAUUCUGGACACAUAAGAACAGUAGGUGUUAAAAACUCAUAUCCCUUAAACUGAGUGUAGGGAAUGGGAUAUUGACAGAAUCUGAAAGCAUGACCUGCACUUUCAUUGUACUGAAACUUCACUUUAUAUCUAAAUCAUGCUGUUUCUGAAACAGCUUCCUAGUUUGUAAAUAGACUUACUUGGUAUAUUUUUAUUUUGGGAAAAACGUUUGCAGAAAUGUAAGUAAAGCCAAUCUGCAAAACUGUAUAGCUUUGACAAUUCCAUAUUGUAAAUACUGUGUAAAUCUUGUUGAAAUAGAGGUUAAAUCAACCUAAUGUUCUUACACUGUGUUUUUUGACUUCUUAUGAUCCCUAAUUCUGAGACUUACUCAUCUGGAAUAGUUUCUCACUUGUUUUGGAGGAAAAUGAUGCUUAUUCUUAUAAAUUACCUUCAGUAACUAUUCAAUAAGACAUUUAAAUACACAAUCACUAAGUACUACAAAAUAAUAACCACCUCAACUGAUAGCAAAAUAUCUAAUUAGAAAUCAACAGUUUGAUGAGUUUUUUUCCUAGAGUGAAUACUACCCCUUUCUUAUAAUUGCUGUAAGUAUUAUAUUUCUGGAAUUUCACACUUUACCUACUCUGAUCACUCUGUUCUCUUUGUUUUAAAGAGAGAAUUUUGUAAACCAUUUAUUGAAUGUUCUGAUCUUUCAUUUAUAACUUAAGAUUUUUUACAGAACUUUAAGUGGUUAGACUAUUGAGCCAUAAAAUUUUGGUUUGUAGUAGAGAUUUCUCGGUAUGUACUUUUCCCCUAAAUGCUGGGGAUUUAAAGAAUUGCACUAAUUCAUAGAACUCUUUACAUUGUAGUGACCAAUGCACAUAUAAUUUAAAUCUUGUGUUCUAUGUGAGAGUUUAUGUGGAGGAUUAUCUUCUGGUGUUGUGUCCAUCAUAAGAUGUAAAAAGAGAAAUCAUAGUUUUAUAUUUUAGUUUCUCCUACAAUGGGUAUGUUAAAUAACUAUAUCUAUACUUAGAUAUAGUGCAUUGUCUGUGUCCCUUAAAGUGUUACAAAGAGUUUCUCUCAAAAGGUCCUUAAGGAGAGUGAGAGAUGAGAGAGGUGCCUUCUCUGUAUUAGACUCACACACAUCAGUCCAGUUGAAGAAUUGGUUUAAACUUUUAAAUGAGAACAGAAAUUAUAAUUAGUACCUGACCAAUUGUGCCUAGAUAUUAAAGUAUGUUCUCUUUAGUACUUUCCGUUCAAUUAAAUAUCAGUAUAUUAGGGAUUUUUUUCUACAGGUGUAUAUUUUGUUGAAGAGUCACUUUCCUCAACCAUUUUUUUGUACUGGGCCUUUAAAAAAAUAAAUCCAUCCAACUUUAACACAACAUUUCUCAGUGUAGAAAUCAUGUCUUCUUAAUUGCUGAACCUUACUGCAAAAACUUGUGAUGUAAGAAAUUUGUAUGGUGUGGCAGUGGUCUAUUCCUAAGGAACUAAAUAUCAUAUAGUUAAUGUUUAUUUAACUCAGCUUGAGACUGUACUACAGUUAGGUUUGAAUAAAUAUUUUCAUUAACUUCAAAAGUUUGAAUUACUUUACAUUGGCAGUCUUGUUUAGAAACUGAUUAAAUUCCUUUGCAAGUCAGUUCUUUUUGGGAGUUUGUACAAUGCUGAAAAUCACAGUUUUCUUCUUAUUCAAUUCAUAGUUGUAUGUACUAAGCACUGAAAAUUCAUAUACAAAUAAAAUAAGUUUACUUUC